AUGUUGGGCCAGGCGUGGUGGCUCAUGCCUCUGGGGCGAGGGGAUAGGCCGAGUUCCGGGUGUAAGGGGGCCAUUAGGGAGAGCAGAGCGAGGCAGCUGAUCUUCCGGAUUGGGGGCCUUGCCCGGAAGCUGGACCUCACGGAGAUGAAACGGAAGAUGCACGAGGAUAUGAUCUCCAUACAGAACUUUCUCAUCUACGUGGCCCUGCUGCGAGUCACUCCAUUUAUCUUAAAGAAAUUGGACAGCAUAUGA